CUGCUGGGGUGAGCAGCACUGUAAAGAUGAAGCUGGCUAACUGGUACUGGCUGAGCUCAGCUGUUCUUGCCACUUACGGUUUUUUGGUUGUGGCAAACAAUGAAACAGAGGAAAUUAAAGAUGAAAGAGCAAAGGAUGUCUGCCCAGUGAGACUAGAAAGCAGAGGGAAAUGCGAAGAGGCAGGGGAGUGCCCCUACCAGGUAAGCCUGCCCCCCUUGACUAUUCAGCUCCCGAAGCAAUUCAGCAGGAUCGAGGAGGUGUUCAAAGAAGUCCAAAACCUCAAGGAAAUCGUAAAUAGUCUAAAGAAAUCUUGCCAAGACUGCAAGCUGCAGGCUGAUGACAACGGAGACCCAGGCAGAAACGGACUGUUGUUACCCAGUACAGGAGCCCCGGGAGAGGUUGGUGAUAACAGAGUUAGAGAAUUAGAGAGUGAGGUUAACAAGCUGUCCUCUGAGCUAAAGAAUGCCAAAGAGGAGAUCAAUGUACUUCAUGGUCGCCUGGAGAAGCUGAAUCUUGUAAAUAUGAACAACAUAGAAAAUUAUGUUGACAGCAAAGUGGCAAAUCUAACAUUUGUUGUCAAUAGUUUGGAUGGCAAAUGUUCAAAGUGUCCCAGCCAAGAACAAAUACAGUCACGUCCAGUUCAACAUCUAAUAUAUAAAGAUUGCUCUGACUACUACGCAAUAGGCAAAAGAAGCAGUGAGACCUACAGAGUUACACCUGAUCCCAAAAAUAGUAGCUUUGAAGUUUACUGUGACAUGGAGACCAUGGGGGGAGGCUGGACAGUGCUGCAGGCACGUCUCGAUGGGAGCACCAACUUCACCAGAACAUGGCAAGACUACAAAGCAGGCUUUGGAAACCUCAGAAGGGAAUUUUGGCUGGGGAACGAUAAAAUUCAUCUUCUGACCAAGAGUAAGGAAAUGAUUCUGAGAAUAGAUCUUGAAGACUUUAAUGGUGUCGAACUAUAUGCCUUGUAUGAUCAGUUUUAUGUGGCUAAUGAGUUUCUCAAAUAUCGUUUACACGUUGGUAACUAUAAUGGCACAGCUGGAGAUGCAUUACGUUUCAACAAACAUUACAACCACGAUCUGAAGUUUUUCACCACUCCAGAUAAAGACAAUGAUCGAUAUCCUUCUGGGAACUGUGGGCUGUACUACAGUUCAGGCUGGUGGUUUGAUGCAUGUCUUUCUGCAAACUUAAAUGGCAAAUAUUAUCACCAAAAAUACAGAGGUGUCCGUAAUGGGAUUUUCUGGGGUACCUGGCCUGGUGUAAGUGAGGCACACCCUGGUGGCUACAAGUCCUCCUUCAAAGAGGCUAAGAUGAUGAUCAGACCCAAGCACUUUAAGCCAUAAAUCACUCUGUUCAUUCCUCCAGGUAUUCGUUAUCUAAUAGGGCAAUUAAUUCCUUCAGCACUUUAGAAUAUGCCUUGUUUCAUAUUUUUCAUAGCUAAAAAAUGAUGUCUGACGGCUAGGUUCUUAUGCUACACAGCAUUUGAAAUAAAGCUGAAAAACAAUGCAUUUUAAAGGAGUCCUUUGUUGUUAUGCUGUUAUCCAAUGAACACUUGCAAGCAAUUAGCAAUAUUGAGAAUUAUACAUUAGAUUUACAAUUCUUUUAAUUUCUAUUGAAACUUUUUCUAUUGCUUGUAUUACUUGCUGUAUUUAAAAAAUAAUUGUUGGCUGGGUGUGGUAGCUCACGCCUGUAAUCCCAGCACUUUGGAAUGUCAAGGCAGGCAGAUCACUUGAGGUCAGGAGUUUGAGACCAGCCUGGCCAAACAUGUGAAACGCUGUCUCUAUUAAAAAUACAAAAAUUAGCCGGGCAUGGUGGUACAUGCCUGUAAUCCUAGCUACUUGGGAGGCUGAGGCAGGAGAAUCGCUUGAACCUGAGAGGAAGAGGUUGCAGUGAGCCAAGACUGAGCCACUGCACUCCAGCAUGGGUGACAGAGAAAACUCUGUCUCAAACAAAAAAAUAAUAAAAUUUAUUCAGUAGGCUGGAUUCUACACAAAGUAAUCUGUAUUUGGGCCAUGAUUUAAGCACAUCUGAAGGUAUAUCACUCUUUUCAGGCUAUAAUUAUUUGGGUAAUCUUCAUUCUGAGACAAACUUAAUCUAUAUCAUUUACUUUGCAACAGAACAACCCUACAGCAUUUUGGUUCCCAGACUAAGGGAACUAAUAUCUAUAUAAUUAAACUUGUUCAUUUAUCAUUCAUGAAAUAUAAAAUACUUGUCAUUUAAACCGUUUAAAAAUGUGGUAGCAUAAUGUCACCCCAAAAAGCAUUCAGAAAGCAAUGUAACUGUGAAGACCAGGGUUUAAAGGUAAUUCAUUUAUAGUUUAUAACUCCUUAGAUGUUUGAUGUUGAAAACUGCUUUAACAUGAAAAUUAUCUUCCUCUGCUCUGUGUGAACAAUAGCUUUUAAUUUAAGAUUGCUCACUACUGUACUAGACUACUGGUAGGUUUUUUUGGGGGGGGUGGGUAGGGAUAUGUGGGUAAUGAAGCAUUUACUUACAGGCUAUCAUACUCUGAGGCCAAUUUUAUCUCCAAAGCAAUAAUAUCAUUAAGUGAUUCACUUCAUAGAAGGCUAAGUUUCUCUAGGACAGAUAGAAAACAUGAAUUUUGAAAUAUAUAGAACAGUAGUUAAAAUACUAUAUAUUUCAACCCUGGCUGGUAGAUUGCUUAUUUUACUAUCAGAAACUAAAAGAUAGAUUUUUACCCAAACAGAAGUAUCUGUAAUUUUUAUAAUUCAUCAAUUCUGGAAUGCUAUAUAUAAUAUUUAAAAGACUUUUUAAAUGUGUUUAAUUUCAUCAUCGUAAAAAGGGAUCAUCUCAGAGAGAACAGCAGUAUUCUGCGUAUUUUUAAAAAUGCUCUAGAGUAACAUUUGAAGUAAUUCACUGUAGUGUAUGCCAGUCCUAGAAAUAAUUUUUUUAAUUUCUGGUGUCUGUUUCUAAUACACUAACCAAGUUUUCAAAAUAUAUUUACAAAGAUGCAUCUUUACCCAUUAUUUUAAAAUGAUUAAGGAGGAUAGUUGCUUCAGGUAACAAGCUAAUUUUUCAAAUAUUAGGCCCUUACAGAACUAUUUAGUCAAAAAGUAAGAUAUUCCUUUAAAAUAUAUAACCCAAAGCUUUCAGUUAAACAUGAUAUAUCACAAAUACUAUUAAAAUGUUAAAGAGAAAUGCAAAUAGCAUUAAAUGAUGACCAAAAUGUAAAAUAUUGUAGAUUUCAAAAGCUGUGUCUCUAUUAGGUGGGAUACCAAAUGUAAAUGAUGUAACUGACGUUGUUUUUUACUUUUUACUUUUUAAAAAAGACUAAAAACGUUUUGAUAUUAUACAAUGUAUUUGUUUCAGAUAAGGUCAUUGUCAUUUAGUAUAUAUAAUUAAUAUAUGUACAAGUUUAAGUAAAUUCCUGUGAGUAAAAAUGGACUUAUCACAAAACAUAGUUCUAAAGAAAGGUAUAUGCUCAUAUACACGGUGUCCAUUAAUUUAAUGGGAACUAGGUAUAACUUCAGGAGAAUUUGGCAAAUAAUUCAUUAAUCCAUGUAAAUAUUCAAAAGCUUGUUCUAUCCACAUUAUUUCAAGGGAUCACUUUAUUUUUCAUUAUACUUUCACAGCACUUUUCUAGUAAAUUCUGUAACACAGAAAUUCCAUUUUGGAAUCAUUUCAUGUUACCAAUAAUUCUAGACUUUUAUAACAUUUAACAUGUUGAUGGAAAUAGAUUACAUCUGCUAGAACCUUUUGCCUUAACUAUUCACCAAUAUAUGCUAAUAUUCAUAAAUAUGGAUUGACUGUUUACAAACAUUAGAAUCUUGUCUUGGUUCCAUUUUGAUGGCUAAUAUUUGUUAUCUUAAUUAAGACUAUUUCUGAGGUCAUGAUUACUUGAAAAUAUUGACUAAAACUGGGUCCUUAGAAAUUCCAGGUGGAGCUGAUUUACCUAUGACUGAGGGGAAAAAAAAAUCAAAUUUUACUGAUAAUAGUAAUGCUCCAAAUGAAUUAAUGACACAUCUGUUCAAUAAAUAAAGAGCUUAAAUAUACAAAACAUAAGAAAUCUGGGCAACAAAACUUGUGGUCUUUACUUUUGAAUAGCUACCCAAGAAAAGGUUUUAAAGGUAAAAGUUAUGAGUAAUGUCAUCACAAUAAGCUCUUGUUUAAAAUUCUUUUCUUUUAUGUAUAAUUAGGUUUAUGUUUCAUGUCUUUUUAAAACCUUAUAAAAGAUUUAAUUAUCACAUCUAUUCUUCAAUGUGGAAAUAUUAAAUAUUGUUGGUUGUAAAAUAAUA